AGCCCUUGCGCGCCACCGUCCCUUCUCUCUUCCUCGGCGCUGCCUACGGAGGUGGCAGCCAUCUCCUUCUCGGCAUCAUGGCCGCCCUCAGACCCCUUGUGAAGCCCAAGAUCGUCAAAAAGAGAACCAAGAAGUUCAUCCGGCACCAGUCAGACCGAUAUGUCAAAAUUAAGCGUAACUGGCGGAAACCCAGAGGCAUUGACAACAGGGUUCGUAGAAGAUUCAAGGGCCAGAUCUUGAUGCCCAACAUUGGUUAUGGAAGCAACAAAAAAACAAAGCACAUGCUGCCCAGUGGCUUCCGGAAGUUCCUGGUCCACAACGUCAAGGAGCUGGAAGUGCUGCUGAUGUGCAACAAAUCUUACUGUGCCGAGAUCGCUCACAAUGUUUCCUCCAAGAACCGCAAAGCCAUCGUGGAAAGAGCUGCCCAACUGGCCAUCAGAGUCACCAACCCCAAUGCCAGGCUGCGCAGUGAAGAAAAUGAGUAGGCAGCUCAUGUGCACGUUUUCUGUUUAAAUAAAUGUAAAAACUGCCAUCUGGCAUCUUCCUUCCUUGAUUUUAAGUCUUCAGCUUCUUGGCCAACUUAGUUUGCCACAGAGAUUGUUCUUUUGCUUAAGCCCCUUUGGAAUCUCCCAUUUGGAGGGGAUUUGUAAAGGACACUCAGUCCUUGAACAGGGGAAUGUGGCCUCAAGUGCACAGACUAGCCUUAGUCAUCUCCAGUUGAGGCUGGGUAUGAGGGGUACAGACUUGGCCCUCACACCAGGUAGGUUCUGAGACACUUGAAGAAGCUUGUGGCUCCCAAGCCACAAGUAGUCAUUCUUAGCCUUGCUUUUGUAAAGUUAGGUGACAAGUUAUUCCAUGUGAUGCUUGUGAGAAUUGAGAAAAUAUGCAUGGAAAUAUCCAGAUGAAUUUCUUACACAGAUUCUUACGGGAUGCCUAAAUUGCAUCCUGUAACUUCUGUCCAAAAAGAACAGGAUGAUGUACAAAUUGCUCUUCCAGGUAAUCCACCACGGUUAACUGGAAAAGCACUUUCAGUCUCCUAUAACCCUCCCACCAGCUGCUGCUUCAGGUAUAAUGUUACAGCAGUUUGCCAAGGCGGGGACCUAACUGGUGACAAUUGAGCCUCUUGACUGGUACUCAGAAUUUAGUGACACGUGGUCCUGAUUUUUUUUGGAGACGGGGUCUUGCUCUCACCCAGGCUGGGAGUGCAGUGGCACACUGACUACAGCCUUGACCUCCCCAGGCUCAGGUGAUCUUCCCACCUCAGCCUUCCAAGUAGCUGGGACUACAGAUGCACACCUCCAAACCUGGGUAGUUUUUGAAGUUUUUUUGUAGAGGUGGUCUAGCCAUGUUGCCUAGGCUCCCGAACUCCUGAGCUCAAGCAAUCCUGCUUCAGCCUCCCAAAGUACUGGGAUUACAGGCAUCUUCUGUAGUAUAUAGGUCAUGAGGGAUAUGGGAUGUGGUACUUAUGAGACAGAAAUGCUUACAGGAUGUUUUUCUGUAACCAUCCUGGUCAACUUAGCAGAAAUGCUGCGCUGGGUAUAAUAAAGCUUUUCUACUUCUAGUCUAGACAGGAAUCUUACAGAUUGUCUCCUGUUCAAAACCUAGUCAUAAAUAUUUAUAAUGCAAACUGGUCAUUUUUGGGAUUUUGUUUUUGAGACUCAUUCUGUCACCCCGGCUGGAGUGCAGUGGCUUGAUCUUGGCUCCCUGCAACUUCUGCCUCCUGGGUUCAGGCGAUUCGAUUAACAAUUGGAGACGAGUCGUGCAGAGGAAAGAAGUAACUUAGAAUCUAAUCUUUAUUAACCUGGGAUAUCACAGAAAAUACUUGGGCCUGCCACUUGUAUUUCUUUGUCCUCAAUACUGAACACUAGACACAUUUGAAACCUUCCUCAGAAGGAAACAAACCAACUGGUUAUGCCUGGGUGGUGGCAUGGAAGAUGCCCAUUGUUGCCCAAUUUGCUAAUAAGUAUUUUGAAAUUAGAAAUGAAACAUGAGGUCCAAGCCUGUCCAGUUCCCUACCCAACCCAUUCCUCCUCCCUGGAAAAAAGAAACCCGUAUCAUCUUCCAAAUUUCUGAUUCAUCACUGCCACUUAAAAA